AGGUUUCUUAAGUUGGUUUUAGAAGUUGCUUAGUCAUGUCUGGCCGUGGUAAAGGUGGAAAAGGUUUGGGUAAGGGAGGAGCUAAGCGUCAUCGCAAGGUUUUGCGCGAUAACAUCCAGGGCAUCACUAAGCCAGCUAUCCGGCGCCUUGCUCGUCGCGGCGGUGUCAAGCGAAUUUCUGGCCUUAUCUAUGAGGAGACUCGUGGUGUUCUGAAGGUGUUCCUGGAGAACGUGAUUCGUGACGCUGUCACUUACACAGAGCACGCCAAACGCAAGACCGUGACAGCAAUGGAUGUGGUCUACGCGCUGAAGCGACAGGGACGCACUCUUUACGGCUUCGGUGGCUAAGGCUCCUGCUUGCUGCACUCUUAUUUUCAUUUUCAACCAAAGGCCCUUUUCAGGGCCGCCCA